AUGUACAGCAAGCCCAGACCGCAAAAAGAUUCGCGAAGGGCAGAAUAUGCCGGCUUCUUCGGUUCGCCGCCGCCUUCAGCCCAGGAUGUCUCCGAACCCUGGAGCCGAACAGGCUGGGUCUCCCCAGCGCGUUCCAUCGCGGCUCAGUCUCACCACUCCGCGCGCUGCCCGCCCCUCCGCGCCCCUGGACUCGUGUCUCCAUUUCUCCAGACCGUCCGCGAUCCCCCAACUCAGCCCCGAGAGAAGUGUGUGGAGGGCGAGAAGGGGACCGCAGAGGGGCACCCGGAUCCCGGAGCCCAGCCUCCACCCCUUUCCUGUCGCCCCAGCACCCGGAGCCUCCCCGCCUGCCUGUCCUAUCCCUCUAUCUCCCUAUCAGAGUUCCGCCAGCCCCGGCUGCAAGGUCGCGGAUCUCUGAACAGCAGUAUAGUCCCCCAGUGGGGGAAACCUCACCCAGGAUGGGUUACUGCAAACAUUGCAAGAACUUGGGGGGAAAGUUGCCAUAUUUGUUCUUUGGCACCCUGGAAUCGACGUGCGGGCGGGCGCGCGCGCGCGCACACACACUCCCACCCUCGCCCAGCACGCCCGGAGAAAACGUCUCUCGACGGUGGAGGCACUGUCUUCAAGUCCCUGUCGACCCACCCCCUUCGCCCAUCCAUCACCCUCCUGCAGCUCCGCGACCCACUCACCCUCCCACGGCAUCCCCUCGGCUCCGGGACUGACAGACGCAAGCACACACCCUCCGAGCGUCUGCGCGCCCGCCGCGCCAGAGGGGCUCCGCGGUCUGCGCCCGCCGCCGCCGCGGCGCGGGGCAACUGGGAAAAAAAAGUUCUGCUCAGACUACCCGUGAGCCGACCGACUACCAGUGAGCCGACCGACCACCAGCCGACCCGGGCGCCGACUCCCUGCUCCUUACCUCGGUCUGGGGGCCACGGGAGCGCGCCGGUCCCGUCCGCACUGCAGCCAGCUGGAAGCAGCCCCUCUCCUGCCGGCCCGCUCCCUCCGGCCCCUCCCCGCCCCCCACGGGUGUUUGCCCGGCGGCAAAGCGGGUUCUUCCAGGGCAAGUGCAAACUGUCUGAGGAGGAAAAAAUUACUUCUAGGAUGAAGCAUUUUACCUCUUUUUCAUUUUCUAAGAUGAUCUCUCAGAUACCUUGCGAAGCCACGCAGAACAAAAGGGAGUCAUUACAUAUUUGGAAAAUGCAUUGGACCUCAUGAUUUGGGAAUGAGCUAUAAGACUGACAGCUGGGACAGCUAAUUUAAGAGUAGAAUUCUUUAGGUCCUGUACCUUAAAGGAAAAGACAGUUUUCAGGAGCUGCCAUUAAGAAUAAUCUGAGG